AGAGCUACGCGGCGAAUGGCGGAGACGCUGAGGCGGGUGCUAACCAGGGGCGGUGCGGCCUGGUCCGGGGAGGAGAACAUGCCUGCCGCCGGACCGCCUUUGCUGCUGCUCGGUACACCAGGAUCUGGAAAAACAGCGCUGCUAUUUGCUGCGGCCCUAGAGGCGGCGGGGGAGGGCCAAGGCCCAGUCCUCUUCCUGACACGAAGGCCUCUUCAAAGCAUGCCCCGCGGGACCGGAACGACUCUAGACCCAAUGCGACUCCAGAAGAUCCGCUUCCAGUACCCACCCUCAACCCGAGAGCUUUUCCGGCUCCUGUGCUCUGCCCAUGAGGCCCCGGGGCCAGCCCCCUCCCUUCUGCUGCUCGACGGCCUAGAAGAGUACCUAGCGGAAGACCCAGAGCCCCAGGAAGCCGCCUACCUCAUUGCCUUACUUCUAGACACAGCUGCCCACUUCAGCCACCGGCUUGGGCCUGGCCGGGAUUGUGGGCUCAUGGUGGCCCUCCAGACCCAGGAGGAAGCAGGUAGUGGGGACGUCCUGCACCUGGCACUGCUCCAGCGGUAUUUUCCUGCCCAGUGCUGGCUGCAGCCAGAUGCACCAGGUCCAGGAGAGCACGGCCUCCGAGCCUGCCUGGAGCCAGGCGGGCUGGGCCCCAGAACAGAGUGGUGGGUGACUUUCCGAUCAGAUGGAGAAAUGAUGAUCGCUCCGUGGCCCACCCAGGCUGGUGACCCCAGCUCAGGCAAGGGUUCAAGCUCUGGAGGCCAGCCCUGAGCUUUGGUGGGUGACUACCUCUCUGUGCUUCAGUUUCCCAUGGCUGGAAUACUUACCUCAGGGACAUAUGCAGAUCCAAAGACCUAAACAAUGUAAAGUGCUUUUUCUCUUUUAAAAGUAUAGCAUUAUCUUGUAUAUAUUUUACCCAAUCAA